AUAACACCCGCGACCCCGCAGCUAAGCGCAGCUCCCGACGCAAUGGACCCGGCGCUGGCAGCCCAGAUGAGCGAGGCUGUGGCCGAGAAGAUGCUCCAGUACCGGCGGGACACAGCAGGCUGGAAGAUUUGCCGGGAAGGCAAUGGAGUUUCAGUUUCCUGGAGGCCAUCUGUGGAGUUUCCAGGGAACCUGUACCGAGGAGAAGGCAUUGUAUAUGGGACACUAGAGGAGGUGUGGGACUGUGUGAAGCCAGCUGUUGGAGGCCUACGAGUGAAGUGGGAUGAGAAUGUGACCGGUUUUGAAAUUAUCCAAAGCAUCACUGACACCCUGUGUGUAAGCAGAACCUCCACUCCCUCCGCUGCCAUGAAGCUCAUUUCUCCCAGAGAUUUUGUGGACUUGGUGCUAGUCAAGAGAUAUGAGGAUGGGACCAUCAGUUCCAACGCCACCCAUGUGGAGCAUCCGUUAUGUCCCCCGAAGCCAGGUUUUGUGAGAGGAUUUAACCAUCCUUGUGGUUGCUUCUGUGAACCUCUUCCAGGGGAACCCACCAAGACCAACCUGGUCACAUUCUUCCAUACCGACCUCAGCGGUUACCUCCCACAGAACGUGGUGGACUCCUUCUUCCCCCGCAGCAUGACCCGGUUUUAUGCCAACCUUCAGAAAGCAGUGAAGCAAUUCCAUGAGUAAUGCUAUCGUUACUUCUUGGCAAAGAACUCCCGUGACUCAUCGAGGAGCUCCAGCUGUUGGGACACCAAGGAGCCUGGGAGCACGCAGAGGCCUGUGUUCACUCUUUGGAACAAGCUGAUGGACUGCGCAUCUCUGAGAAUGCCAACCAGAGGCGGCAGCCCACCCUUCCUGCCUCCUGCCCCACUCAGGGUUGGCGUGUGAUGAGCCAUUCAUGUGUUCCAAACUCCAUCUGCCUGUUACCCAAACACGCCUCUCCUGGCAGGGUAGACCCAGGCCUCUAACCAUCUGACAGAGACUCGGCCUGGACACCAUGCGAUGCACUCUGGCACCAAGGCUUUAUGUGCCCAUCACUCUCAGAGACCACGUUUCCCUGACUGUCAUAGAGAAUCAUCAUCGCCACUGAAAACCAGGCCCUGUUGCCUUUUAAGCAUGUACCGCUCCCUCAGUCCUGUGCUGCAGCCCCCCAAAUAUAUUUUUCUGAUAUAGACCUUGUAUAUGGCUUUAAUGCCGCAAAAUAUUUAUUUUUCCUUAAAAAAGGUGUCAACUUGGAAAUAAUGGUUUAAAAACAGGAUAAGCAUUAAGGAAAAACACUUUCAAUGUGUCUUCCAUUUGAUGAAUUUGUUUUUCUCUCUUUAUCCCCGCAAGGUGGAGUUUCAUGUCCUCGGUGAAACCAGACAGUGUGAAUCUGUUCCAGCCCAAAUCUGCAGCAUUAGGGAUGAGUUCUCAGAAGUGAUUCUGAACUGAGCACGCACUCAUGUCUGCAUGGGGAACUCUGGGGAGAAGAGCCUUCCUUUUCUUUCCCUUGGGCAUUUGCCUUUCCUUGUCGUCUUACUGAGGCGGAGGCAGGAGGUCUCUGUCUUCCAGGCCCUGGCCAGGCCAUCCUGCCAUCAGGAAAGAUGGAAGAGUAGGCCUCCGUCUAGCAGCCCUGGCUGGAAAUCCCCCCUCUAGAUCCUGCUGCAAGACUGUACAAACUCACAGGGGCCAUGUCCACCCAGGCACAUCAUCAGAACCAGGGAGCACAGCCUUGCCACCUAGAAGGGGCCUCAGCAGCCGUGCAACUUUCUUUCCCUAUCUCCAAUCCAGAGAGGGAUCCUCUAACAUUCUCUAGCAACCUCAUCUGCACCCCCACCACCUUCCUUGUAAGAAAGACCACGUGUGACUAAAAUCCCUUCACGCUGCAUUUACCCAGGUUACUAUUGUGCGCGCAAAAUGUUUUCACAGUGUUCUCAGCCUUUGCUCCUCCAAACAGAAAACGUUUCCCCUGCGUUACUGUUACUUCCCUAUUUUUGAGUCCUGGGGUGACUGUCUCUUAAAUGUGCCAAGAUGUGAGCAAGCUUUAAAACAUGACAGCUCAGUGUUAAGGAGACAGAAAGCUUCCUCUUUCUCUGUUCUAUUGCAACUACAAAUUCUACAGUCAUGCCUAAGAUCCUUUAGCUAACACCCUUUUCAAGAAAUCAUCAGACUCUUGGAUUGACUUAGAAUUCAUUCAUUCAUUAAGUGCUUACCGAGUCCCCGCUCUGUGGCAAGCACUGUUCUAUAUCAACUUCUCAUGAGUUCAGCCAAUUCUAGGUGCACCAGCCAAGGAAACUUCAUGCCUGCCCUCUCUGAGCUCCAUACUCUGAGGUGGUGGUCUUAUCAAGAUGGGAUCGCCUUGUACAUCCCUGUGUAGCCAAGUGGAAGGCCAGCCAACCAAGAAUGCAUCUCACUGGGCCUAUGGGACAUACUGUGCCUGCACUGCUCCUCCACGUGACUGCAUCAGGUUAAACUGGUCAGAGCCCUGGAUGAGGAGCUGGAAAACAUGCAUCCAGUCCAAGCUCUGCCACUUGGGCCAAGUGUGCUCUUGAACAGUCACUUAAUAUAUCUGCUUUGAUUUGUCUUUUAAAGAAAAUAUGGAGGCAGGAAUACCAGUGUCAGUGUAGCCUGCUUCUUGAGUGUUGGCACAAGUGAGAUAAUGUAUGAAUCAGUAAAAUGCUGGGCAAAGCAAAGAAGUAGGGCUGCCUGGGAGUGGAUUCCUUUUUAUGGUGAGUUAAGACGACUUCACAAUUGUUAGCUGUGAUGCCUGCAGUGUUUGAGGAUGGCAUUGCCUUCAUCCUGUGUCAGCUCUGAAGAAGUUGGCAGAGCAAAGCUAAGCCUCAAGUGUAAAUCCCAGCAUCAUGGAACGCAAAUGGAUGAGCUUUUGUUUUAGGAUCUUCUUGCUGAUUCCUACCCAGAGGACUUCCCCAGCCUAGAGACCAGAAACCUGGGCAAUAGUUAUAUCUUCAGUGGCCCUAGGAGUUGUUGUGUCUCCUUGGGGAGGAGAGAACCUUCUAAAACAGGCCAGAGACAGGAGGUACUGGGAGGGCCAUGGGCUCACCUGCAUCUAUGCCCAGAUAACCUGGGACAGAUAACCUCUGUCCCAAUCACUUGCUUUGCCUGGUCUCUCAAGGAGUCUCUUGGUACCCCAGGCCCACGGCCAGCUCCAUGCUCAUCCCUGUCCCCACCUUCCAGUCUUGAUGAAAACCCACCUUCUCUUUCAUCCCUUGGCUGCUUGAUAAGACUUAAAACAAUUCCCUGAUUUUAGGGAAGGCCACUGCGUGCACAGAUGGUGAGUUUGUGCAGGCAAGGAAUGUGCCCUCCACAUCACGUGGCCUCCUUGCCCAGCCUGGGUCAUGGGAAGGGAGUGUUGAAUUGAAUCACGUCUUUCGUUGGUAGAUUAUGUUCAUCUUCAAUGUUUCUAUUAAGUCUAAAAAGUGGAUACAAAUGGUGCCUCCAAGUUCUUGUCUAAUUGCUUGUCUACUGCUUGACAAAAUCCAGAAUGGAAUAGGCCAAACAAGUUAACCAGCAGGACAGAAACUGCUCUAAGCCCAUUAUUCCUUGAGAUGAAUAGAACAGUGAGCUGAACGCCUGCUCUAAUGAAGCCACUAAAGGGGUUUACAGGAAGGUUAGGAGCCCAGAUGGGUUUUGAGUCCACUGCUGGGAAACAGAUUCUUCACUUCCUGUGGACCCUGGAGAAGCCAUCAGAUUACAUUAACAUGGCUCCACUGAUGAUGGCCUGAGAAUUACUAUUGUUUGUGUUUCAUCUGUGUCCUUGCCAGGUCUUCCCCCACAUCCUUACUUCACAGGAUCAGGGGCUGAGAGGAGACCAAUACUCUGGCCCAGGCCUGGUCAAGGGAUGCUGGUUGUUGCUGAUGCAAAGUCACAUUGCCUGGUCCUGAGCUUGGCAAUCAGGCAUCCAGAGAUGGCCAAACCAAAUAUCCCUUUGGCCAGGCACUCAGGCAUUCCCUGUAAUGUUGUGCACUUAAAGCAUCUUGGGCUGAUAGUCUCCACCGAAUCACAGAAGAAAACUCAAUCUGCCGCAUCACUCACCAGCUGGAUAAGCCAUUUACUGUACACAGUGUGUGCCCUCUUAUCAAUACAUUGGCACAGAACCAUACACCGUAGAAGCUGCUGUGAUCACUAAAGGCAAUGCCCGUUUAGCCCUGAGCACAGUGCUUGGCAUGUGGUAGGUAAGUAGUAGCAAUUUUAUUUGAUACCCUCAUAUACACGCUGGUUCCUUCUGUCGGCACACCUGUCCACGCUUUGAGCUUGGUGCUUCACCUGUACUCCUCUGUUUACUGGCUCCACCACCCUUCCCUAGGAUUACUUCUCCAAUCCAACCAAAAACAAUUUUGCAAAUGUUUCAUGUGACAAACUGUAUUUUUCAUAAAUGACCCCAGCAAUAUUUCCUCUCCCCUUAAACCCAGGCAGGUUUGUGUCAGCUCUAACUGAUGGAGUAUGGUGGAGGUGAUGCCAUGCAACUUCCAAGGCAAAGGUAUAAACAAGAUGCAGCUUCUACAUGGCUCUUGCGAUCCUGGGAUGCUCAUCCUGGGAAUCCAGACACCAUGUUGUGAGGAGGCCCAGGCCACAAGGAGAGGCCACCUAUAAGCAUUCAGGCCAGCAGCCCCAGGUGAGUUCCCAGCCAACAUCAACGGCCAGAUGUAUGAGUGAAUGAUCUCACGUGGUCCCAGCCUUUGCAUGACUUUGCAUGACGCCAGCUGAUGCCAAGUGGGACAGAGAUGAGCUGCCCAUUCCAAUCUCUGCCCACAUUGCAGAUUCAUGAGAAAAAUAAAUGUCACUGUUUGGGGGUGAAUCAUGACACAGUUACAGUACUUGAAACAUUUUGCGAAGCCAGGCAUGAAUGUCAUAUGAAAUUCUAAUAAAUCCAUUUUAUUUGUGGCACCACAA